GAGUAGCUGGGACUGUAAGCACACAUCACCAUGCCUGCCUGAUUUUUUGUAUUUUUGUAGACAGGAGGUAUUACCAUGUUGUCCAGGCUGGUCUCCAACUCCUGGGCUCAGGCAGUCUGCCCACCUCGGCUUCCCAAAGUGCUUCAGCCACUAUGCCUGGCCUCUUUUUUUCCUAUAAUGGCUAGUACAGUGCUUGGCGUGUAAUAAGCGCUAAUGAAAUAUUUCUUGAGUACUUGAAUAAGUGAAUAAAUGCAAGUGCUAGAGAACUAAUAAUAAAAGCAUUAUGGAUCCAAGCCUGUUGAGAGAAAGGGAGCUGUUCAAAAAACGAGCUCUUUCUACUCCUGUAGUAGAAAAACGUUCAGCAUCUUCUGAGUCAUCAUCAUCAUCGUCAAAGAAGAAGAAAACAAAGGUAGAACAUGGAGGAUCGUCAGGCUCUAAACAAAAUUCUGAUCAUAGCAAUGGAUCAUUUAACUUGAAAGCUUUGUCAGGAAGCUCUGGAUAUAAGUUUGGUGUUCUUGCUAAGAUUGUGAAUUACAUGAAGACACGGCAUCAGCGAGGAGAUACGCAUCCUCUAACCUUAGAUGAAAUUUUGGAUGAAACACAACAUUUAGAUAUUGGACUCAAGCAGAAACAAUGGCUAAUGACUGAGGCUUUAGUCAACAAUCCCAAAAUUGAAGUAAUAGAUGGGAAGUAUGCUUUCAAGCCCAAGUACAACGUGAGAGAUAAGAAGGCCCUACUUAGGCUCUUAGAUCAGCAUGACCAGCGAGGAUUAGGAGGAAUUCUUUUAGAAGACAUAGAAGAAGCACUGCCCAAUUCCCAGAAAGCUGUCAAGGCUUUGGGGGACCAGAUACUAUUUGUAAAUCGUCCCGAUAAGAAGAAAAUACUUUUCUUCAAUGAUAAGAGCUGUCAGUUUUCUGUGGAUGAAGAAUUUCAGAAACUGUGGAGGAGUGUCACUGUAGAUUCCAUGGACGAGGAGAAAAUUGAAGAAUAUCUGAAGCGACAGGGUAUUUCUUCCAUGCAGGAAUCUGGACCAAAGAAAGUGGCCCCUAUUCAGAGAAGGAAAAAGCCUGCUUCACAGAAAAAGCGACGCUUUAAGACUCAUAACGAACACUUGGCUGGAGUGCUGAAGGAUUACUCUGACAUUACUUCCAGCAAAUAGGGAACAGUUUUGCCCUGGAACAGAGUUACAGAUACACAAUCAAGAGUGUUCUUGCUGAUGCUCGGGGUCUGAAGACUGUCUUCCUAUCUGCUUCUUGCGGCUGAGGAGAGGAGCAGUUCAGUUUACAAAACAAGUGCAAAUUACCAAACUCAAAGCUUAUUUGAGUAGAAUGGGCUCAUGGGCAAUGUGAUGUUCCCUGUUAACCUUCUGUUACUCCCUGGGAGAAAGGCGCUGAGCGUGGCAUGCAGGUGUCUUUGCUGUGUUUUUCUCCACUUCUAAAUGGUUCCUGGUUCCUUUCUUCCUCGUUUGUUACUUUAGAGCAAGUUUGCCCAUAGUCUUGAAUGCAAUAUUUGUUUAUUCCAAAAGAACAUAUUUAUAAUAAAAUCACUGUAGAAGGAUUUUUAAGAUGUUAGUGAAUUCUGUUUCUUUUCAUUCUCGGAAAUGGCAGGAAGCAGCUCCAGUCUCUGAUUUCCAUGGGUCACGUGCUGGGGAUGUGAUGAAGCCUGCAGUCUGCACUGUGUUGCUGAGCACAUGGAUUUCACCACUGGAACACAGGUGUGCUGCUUGUUAGCAAGCAGAGCAAUAAAGAUGUGCUGGAUGUCA